GCCACCGCGCCUCACUGCUUUUAAAUUUUUUCUAUGUGGAGCUCUUACCAUGUUACCUUUCUGGUGUCAUGAAAGCCUUCUCCAGAAAGGUAUAAAAUCCUGUCUUUGACAGAAAUGUAGUUGAAGAGCUGUUACCUUAGAAGAGUCUUUUAGGUUUUUCUUAAAAUUUGAAUCACAUUUAAAAAGAUGUCUUUAAAAUUGAUUAGACUGUUUCUCCACCCAAAUUAUACACUUAUGGGCCAUGUAUUAAUUCAUGAUUAGAUUGAAAAUUGAUUUGCAUAAUGAAAUUAUUUUAACAUCAGUGCUGCUUUAGACAUUCUCUUUGAUCAGGUUGCAUGUAGUAGAAAAAGCUUCUGUCUUUGGCAUUGCAAAAUAUACAGCUUUAUACUUAAAAAAUGAGUUACUUAUUUCUGAUGAGUUUUUGAUCCUAUGCUUGAUGAGAUUUUUUGUAAGUUUAGAUUAUUUAAAGCAGUACAGCAGGAAUCUGAAAUGUGAUGGGACUGCUGUAUUACAUUUAUGACUCUUUAUGGAAUAACUAGAAUUCUUCAUUAAUCUCUUUCCAUAAAAAUUACAGAAUAUUAGAAGUGGAAGGGACCUUGGCAGUCAUUCAUUCCAACUUUCCCUUGGUUGCAAUAGAGAGAAUUUCUAAAUCUUAAGAAAUCAGUGCACAGAACUCAAUCCUGUUGACCAGAUUUACUCCAGCCAGUAUGCGAUGAAGCUGAACAUUUAUGCCACUUGAUCUGAUCUCUAUUCUGCUGCUAAUGAUGUCUAAAGCAAGGGCGAAGGAGGGAGAAAUGCGGGAAGCAGGCACCUAAGAUUUCUUGAACCCCAUCUAAGUAAAAUGUAUUUUACUUAUGUAAUUGUGCUCAAUCCACACCACAACUUAGAAGUUUCCUGUGUGACUCUAAGACUCACUUUUCUUACUGGCAAAUGGGCACAGUAUUUCUUAACUCUGUGGUCACCUGAUUGGUAAAUGUAGAACCAGAAUUUUCUUCUAGGUAUUUCUGAACCUAAAGCUCAUUGUUAUUCCUCCUCUCAAAGAUGAUUGUAUUAAUUCUUGUCAGUCACAUCUUACCAGUGGCUCAUAUUGACUUUUGGUCCCAAUAAUUUUUGAGCGCACAAGGACGGUGUGCUCAGUACAGUACCUGGUACAAAUGCAUGACUUAUAAUUGCACUACUUUCAAGGUUUGGACAAGCUAUAGUGAAGGCUGAGGCUGAAUCAUGAUUUUAUUUUUUCCUAUUGAAUGUUGUUAUCCAAGAGUAAAGUCUGUUGUGCUCUAUAGAGAUCUAAUCGUCAGAUCAAGAUGAUGGGGUUGAUUGUAAGCUCAACUUCUCUCUCCUAUUCUGCUUCAGGCACAUAGAAUGCUAGCUUAAAUAUAUUAAAAUUAAAAUAAUUCAUAUUUAAACUUGUGGGGGAAAACAACACUCCAUGUACCAGAAAUAGAGAACCUAUUGGCAAAGAGAAAUUGAAGCCGUAGGAACUGGGUUCCCAACGCCCAGGGAAGGUUAGGAACUGAAGCCUCAGUUCCCUUGCAAGGAAGGGAGUGAGCACCUGGUCUUGACUAAGCCCCACCUGUGUUCUUCCUAAAUUUAAUGGGAACCAAAAUAUCUCCAGUUGCCAACCUGGCCUAACAGCCAGAAGCAAGUAAAUGGUAAACUUUUCUGGCCAAUUUCCCUUUGGAGGAGGAGUCUUUUUGUCUGUUCCAUUCUUUCUGAGUAAAACUUCUGCUCUCAUUUUGAAUUUCCACUUUGCCUUCUAUUCUUUUUACAAGGGAAGCCAGGCCUGUUAAAGAUGUCAUUAAAGUGUCUUACUGUGAGAUAAGUGGUGCUUGCAGGAAGGUGUGAAUGUGAGUGUUGAUAGGCAUGUUGGACUUAGUAGAGCUGUUCCCCUUACAUUAUGUAUUUCAUUUAUUUUAUUGGCAGCUGAAGUUGGCCUUGUGCUUGCUGACUCAUUUUUAGCAAUUGUGCAAGAAAUGGCAGCAUUUGCCACCUUUGUUUAGUCUCUUCUUUUUCAAAUCACCUUUCAUCAUUUCUUUAUCAUCUUUGGACACCCUGCCAAUUCUUUACUGCCCACAACUUUUGUCUUGCUUACUAGCUAAGGCACUCUUUAUAGGUCAUAGCUAAUGAGGUUGGCUCUAUUCCAUAAAGUAUCUACUGAGUAUCUAGCAUGCACUGAGCAUGGCCUGGGGAAUAUAACAAAAAAAAAAUGUGGGUCAUUUUCCUACCUCAAAAGAGUUUAUGAUGUCAAAGAUGUGCUGCUUCCUGAAGACCCCGUCAACUUUCUGUCUUUUCCCUGGAAGUGUAAAAUGCCACACGUUGGAUGAGAUGAUUAUCCGAGCUCAGACUUGGGAAAUAGUCAUGCUUCUGGACCAAGUGCCAGAUAUAAGAGUUCGGACCGCCCAGCACACAAGGUCAGCAUGCUGCUCCUCUGUCACGCUCUCGCUAUAGCUGUUGUCCAGAUCGUUAUCUUCUCAGAAAGCUGGGCAUUUGCCAAGAACAUCAACUUCUAUAAUGUGAGGCCUCCUCUCGACCCUACACCAUUUCCAAAUAGCUUCAAGUGCUUUACUUGUGAAAACGCAGGGGAUAAUUAUAACUGCAAUCGAUGGGCAGAAGACAAAUGGUGUCCACAAAAUACACAGUACUGUUUGACAGUUCAUCACUUCACCAGCCACGGAAGAAGCACAUCCAUCACCAAAAAGUGUGCCUCCAGAAGUGAAUGUCAUUUUGUCGGUUGCCACCACAGCCGAGAUUCUGAACAUACGGAGUGUAGGUCUUGCUGUGAAGGAAUGAUCUGCAAUGUAGAAUUACCCACCAAUCACACUAAUGCAGUGUUUGCCGUAAUGCACGCUCAGAGAACAUCUGGCAGCAGUGCCCCCACACUCUACCUACCAGUGCUUGCCUGGGUCUUUGUGCUUCCAUUGCUGUGAUGCCACCAUUCCUAGGAGAGGCAGAGACCAGCCUCUAAAGCACAAGCCAAAAACUGUGUGAACGGUGAACUUUGGAGUGAAGAUCAAUCUUGCACUUGGUGAAGAGUGCACAUUGGACCUCAAGGCGAAAGCCAGUGGUUUGCUUGGAUAAAAUGUUCCCGCAUGAGGCCACAGGACUGAGGAUGGGAAUUUGGCAGGGCCUGAGAAGAUGGUCUGACUUCCAGGCUUCCUGGUCAAAGAGAGCUACGUUUGGGCAGUUCUGCAGAGAGGAUCCUGGCAACUAGUCCCACCUGACUAGGCCUUUAGCUGAAAGGAUUUCUUGACCUCCUUGACUGCCUCAGAGGCUGCCAGGUCAAACCCUCUUGUUUAUGUGAUUAGCUCAGAGCAUCUCUAUGAAAUCUAACCCUUCCCCUCAUGAGAAAGCAGUUUUCCCCACCAACAGCAUAGUCAAUGAGAAAGGCAACUGUACGAAGAAAACUUCCAGUGGAACUAAUAUGAAAUCUAUUUGCAAAUUAUGGGGGGAAAUAAAGCUUUUAAAUUAUACAAUGUAAA